AUAAUCAAGGAAACCUUUUCCGGGUGGGGAUCUCUGAAAUUACUCAGAUAACAGUGCUGUGCCAAAAACCUGUGGAUUUUCUCUACAAAAAUUAUCAUGACUGUUAUCUUUUUGAUGGAAAAGAUGAAGUUCAGCGAAGAACAAAUCUACAACUUGGCCAGAAGACUGUAGACUUUGCCUUCAAAGAGUGAGCAACCCUAAUUAACCUGAUUUUUUGCUGAUAAUCACUCUCAAUGGAAUCAAAUCACAAAUCCGGGGAUGGAUUGAGCGGCACUCAGAAGGAAGCAGCCCUCCGCGCACUGGUCCAGCGCACAGGAUAUAGCUUGGUCCAGGAAUUUAGAGGUUCCUAUAGAUGGAAGCAGUGUGUCUGGGCACAUGCCCAGAGCCAGAAGCGAGCAUGAGCACAGCAAUUCCUGGCCUCAAAAAAGGAAAUAAUGCUUUGCAGUCCAUCAUUUUGCAAACUUUGCUGGAAAAGGAAAAUGGACAAAGAAAAUAUGGUGGCCCUCCACCUGGUUGGGAUGCUGCACCCCCUGAAAGGGGCUGUGAAAUUUUUAUUGGAAAACUUCCCCGAGACCUUUUUGAGGAUGAGCUUAUACCAUUAUGUGAAAAAAUCGGUAAAAUUUAUGAAAUGAGAAUGAUGAUGGAUUUUAAUGGCAACAAUAGAGGAUAUGCAUUUGUAACAUUUUCAAAUAAAGUGGAAGCCAAGAAUGCAAUCAAGCAACUUAAUAAUUAUGAAAUUAGAAAUGGGCGCCUCUUAGGGGUUUGUGCCAGUGUGGACAACUGCCGAUUAUUUGUUGGGGGCAUCCCAAAAACCAAAAAGAGAGAAGAAAUCUUAUCGGAGAUGAAAAAGGUUACUGAAGGUGUUGUCGAUGUCAUCGUCUACCCAAGCGCUGCAGAUAAAACCAAAAACCGAGGCUUUGCCUUCGUGGAGUAUGAGAGUCAUCGAGCAGCUGCCAUGGCGAGGAGGAAACUGCUACCAGGAAGAAUUCAGUUAUGGGGACAUGGUAUUGCAGUAGACUGGGCAGAGCCAGAAGUAGAAGUUGAUGAAGAUACAAUGUCUUCAGUGAAAAUCCUAUAUGUAAGAAAUCUUAUGCUGUCUACCUCUGAAGAGAUGAUUGAAAAGGAAUUCAACAAUAUCAAACCAGGUGCUGUGGAGAGGGUGAAGAAAAUUCGAGACUAUGCUUUUGUGCACUUCAGUAACCGAGAAGAUGCAGUUGAGGCUAUGAAAGCUUUAAAUGGCAAGGUGCUGGAUGGUUCCCCCAUUGAAGUCACCCUAGCAAAACCAGUGGACAAGGACAGUUAUGUUAGGUAUACCCGAGGCACAGGUGGAAGGGGCACCAUGCUGCAAGGAGAGUAUACCUACUCUUUGGGCCAAGUUUAUGAUCCCACCACAACCUACCUUGGAGCUCCUGUCUUCUAUGCCCCCCAGACCUAUGCAGCAAUUCCCAGUCUUCAUUUCCCAGCCACCAAAGGACAUCUCAGCAACAGAGCCAUUAUCCGAGCCCCUUCUGUUAGAGAAAUUUACAUGAAUGUACCUGUAGGGGCUGCGGGAGUGAGAGGACUGGGCGGCCGUGGCUAUUUGGCAUACACAGGCCUGGGUCGAGGAUACCAGGUCAAAGGAGACAAAAGAGAAGACAAACUCUAUGACAUUUUACCUGGGAUGGAGCUCACCCCAAUGAAUCCUGUCACAUUAAAACCCCAAGGAAUUAAACUCGCUCCCCAGAUAUUAGAAGAGAUUUGUCAGAAAAAUAACUGGGGACAGCCAGUGUACCAGCUGCACUCUGCUAUUGGACAAGACCAAAGACAGCUAUUCUUGUACAAAAUAACUAUUCCUGCUCUAGCCAGCCAGAAUCCUGCAAUCCACCCUUUCACACCUCCAAAGCUGAGUGCCUUUGUGGAUGAAGCAAAGACGUAUGCAGCCGAAUACACCCUGCAGACCCUGGGCAUCCCCACUGAUGGAGGCGAUGGCACCAUGGCUACUGCUGCUGCUGCUGCUACUGCUUUCCCAGGAUAUGCUGUCCCUAAUGCAACUGCACCCGUGUCUGCAGCCCAGCUCAAGCAAGCGGUAACCCUUGGACAAGACUUAGCAGCAUAUACAACCUAUGAGGUCUACCCAACUUUUGCAGUGACUGCCCGAGGGGAUGGAUAUGGCACCUUCUGAAGAUGCUUUUUUAAAUUUAAGAAUAAGACACACAAAACUCUAUUAAAAAAAAAAAAGAAAUAAACCUCUAACUCGGUCCCCAAUGAUCAUAAAUAAUAUGUUUCCUAAAGAAAUGCCUUUCCAGAGACUGUAUAGCUUAUACCAAUUAUAGAAUCAUGAAGUAAGAACGUUAUUCUGAAAUGAAAUCAAAUGUUAAAGAGCCUUUUGUUUAACAGAAAGCUGGAGAGCCACUGCCCCAAAAGUUGUUCUUCCAGUCUUCCUGAGUGUUUGGGGAGUAUGUUUACAAAUCCUGCCAGGGUGAAGAGAGAUCUUGUAGCUGGCAAGAUUUGGGAGGGAUGGAGCAGACCUGGGCAGUCAGUAAUAAUCAAGGGAAGCCAAGUAAACUCCAGAGUCUUACCUCUGGCUCACAGCUGCUUUUGUGAUACACAAAGUCACAAAGAGGAAAAGGGAAGGGAGGAGGUUGCUUUUCAAAAUGCAUUCACCAUGGCUCACUGUGUGGGGCAUGAUUGCAGGCCUGAGCUCAUGAAAGACUGUCCAAGAUUUUGUGGUUUCAACCUCUCUUCAGCCUGAAAAUUCCAUCCAGUCGAUUUGUCACAGAUCAGGAUCUUCCUGUCCCCUGCAGCCCAUGGGGACUUCCUAGAAAUAGAUAUGAUAUGUUGUAGAUGUGGUUAAAACAAAUCCAGGCCCCAUUGUUUAUUCAGCUCAUUAGUCCACACCUAUUUUUCCCUAGAACUCCUACCUUUUCCAAUAAUCAUGCCAGCAUGAAAUGACCUUUUCUACUUUAAAAUUUUUUGACUUGUUCAUAUUGCUUGAUUUUCAUCAUCUCAGACUCAUUUUUCUCCUACCUAAUAUCAUAAAAAAGUAAAUCAGAUAUACAGAAUAUCAUUUAUGAUACUUCUUCCUUUCAGCAAAUUGACUGAAAAGUCAUUUUAAAGAGAGAAGUGCAGAUUUGCUCUCAUUUCUUUGAUAUUGUUGCAGUAUCCACCCCACCAUCUAGCAAUCAGAGAUGCUUAUAUUAACUUGGGAUUAGCUUUGCAUUAUCUAACCCAUUUAUUUUAAAUCUGCCAGGAAAUCCUCUAACUUUCCUUCCUUUUUGUUUCAGUAAGUAUCAGGCAGCUUCACCAUACCUGAGUCCUUUUGUCUUGAAGCUGCCACAGAAAAAUCUUACAGCAAUCAUUGCUGAUUAGAAACUGUUUCAGACAAUCAGCAUGGGUGUUAUUUACCAAAUUCCCCCCAGAGUCCUAGGCCUCUUCUCCAGAAAUAUCUGAUGAUGAAGUGAGGGGAGGGCAACGGUGCUACAAAACACGGAACAGAGGUAAAGAGAAGGCACUACUUUCUUGCCAUACUUGUAAAUGAUUGCUUUGUUCAAACAUAAAUAAUCUUAAGUCCAACACCAAAUACCUGUUACUCCUACAUCAAUCUCAUUAGUGGUUUAAGACACAGUACUAGAAUUUUCAUUUUUUAAAAUCCCUUGGCCCUUAAAAAAAUUUACAGAACACAAAGGAAAACAUAAACACAAAGACAUGGAAAAUUUUGUCAACUCCUUAAUGGAAUUCUGUGAUCAAAAAGCAGGCCAGAUUCUAAUCAAAAUCAGGUAAAUUUUAAUCACAAUCAGAAGUACUUGUAACAUUUCAGUUGUCCUAACUCCAAUGAGAUAACAAAGCCUCCAAGGCUACAGCUGAAACUCUGAAAGGCCCUGUGCUUUCUACUUUACAUUUAGCGUCUAAUAUUUCCUAGGACAGUAGUUCCCAAAGUAGGCUGUACAUUAGAAUCUCCUGGAGAGCUUUUUAAAUGCUAAUGCCAAUAACAUAUCUCAUAAAAUUUACACUAGAAUUUCCUUGGAUGGGUGCCUGGCAUCAGUAUUUUUUAAUGAUCCCUAGGUGAUUUCAAUGUGCACCUAGGUUUGGGAAUUGCUAUAUUCUUGUAUUUAUACUCUAUCUCUUUAUUUCUUUUCCUUUUUAUUUCACUUUUAGUAAAUAGAAAAAUGCAAUUAAAAAAUCAUCUAAGUUAAGACAAAUAGCCAAAUCAUAUUUAUCCCAUAAAUAGUAUGAAUUUAAAUGUAACUUACGUAGGCUUCAAACUAACUCUAAAAAUGAGAAAGUAAAACAAUCUUGUCCUAAAACAAUUCUUAGAUCCAAAUUUACACUCCCCUACAGAUCUGCUUUUAUUCUCAAAGACAGUGAUUACAUUGACAUAACAAAUGUCCAUUGGGGCAGGCAAAUUUCUACUGAGUCUAAAAAGCAUUCCAAAUUCUAGGAGCAAAAGUUCUGAUUUUCCUUAAAAUCUUUGCAAAUAAACAGCAAAGGGUAUUCUGGAUGUCUUGUCAAUGCAAAUUAGGUUUGAUUUAGAGAAGUUUUAAAUUUAAUCGCAAUGAAAAGAUUAGUUAAUACAUGAAUCUUUUUAUGAGAAAAAAUCAUUAUUCUGGAUAAAGUCAUAAUUGUUUGUUUACAAUAUUAAGAGCAGACACCUAAACAUACAAUAAUACCAAAGUAUUGAGAAAAUUACCACUGGAACACCAUCUCAAGUUAUCACACCAUUUACCUCUUUAGAGCCAGUUUUGUAUAAGUAGGUAGAAGUGGUUUUGGUUUUUUUGCUAAAAUUUUACUUUGUUUUAGUAAUAUCUAGGGAAUACUUUGAAUUCCAUUAAAAUACCUUCAUAGAAAGUGUUAAUGUGUCUACCAUGCCAUAUGUUUAUUUUUACUUUCCCCAAGUUAGGUAGAUAGAGCAAGUCCUGCUACCAUAAGUUUAAAAUUAUUAAGACAACGGGCUUUUUUAAAUUGCUGGUAGAACCAAAGGCUAAUUUUGCAUAGGUUUAUAUUUUUAGACUUAAGAAAUUAGCACCUAUAUAAUACCUUCAUACCUUCUGCAUCACUAUCAAUUUUUCUGUAAUUUCUUAUUUGAAUGCUUCCUAAUUCUUUACAGAAAAAAUUAAAAUUUGUCACCCAACCAGGUGAUAAUAACAAAACAAUAAUUUAGGAACAUCCAGUAAAUUUGAAUUAGUUCUCUAAAUUUUGGUAAUUAAUAGCUUAUUGAUAAUUAAAAUCAGCCUAAUGUUGCUUAAGUAGGAGGAAAUUGAUCAGCAAUGGGAUUGGGUAUCUAUUUUCUUUCCUAUAAAAGUGCUGCCUCUUCUCAAAUUGCUUUAUUUCUCUCCCACUGCAUUAGUAUAUCUAGAACAGCACCUUCAACUGCAACAAAAUAUAAUUCUCCUAGAUGACUAGGAUAUCCUCCAAUCUGGUAUCAUGCCAAACAACACUAUGUUUGGGGAACAGCACCCGAAAUGCUGCUAAAAAGCUACCUCAUGUCAAGAAAAUAUGGAUUUCAAAAAAUAUCUGGCACAGUGGCCCAUGCCUAUAACCCCAGUACUUUGGGAGGCCAAGGCAGGAGGAUUGCUGGAGGCCAGGAGUUCAAGACCAGCCUGGGCAACAUGGAGAGACUCCGCCUCUACAAAAAAAAAAAAAACAAAUUUAAUUUAAUUGGCCAGUUGUGGUGGCGUGGGCCUGUGGUCCCAGCUACUUGGGAAGCUAAGGCAGGAGGAUUGCUGGAGGCCUGGAGGGCAAGGCUGCAGUGAGCCAUGUUCACAUCGCUGCACUCCAGCCUGGGUGACAGAGCAAGACCCUGUCUCCAAAAAAGCAAAAAUAAAUAUCUAACAAAAAGGAACCUGUUUCCAAACCACAGUUUCUUAACUUUUUCAUGAUGGAAUAGAAAUUAAACUAUAAGUAUAUACUGAUAAUAGCUGUGCAGGAAAUUGGUUUUUAUUUUACUUAAAAGUAUUUUUUAGAAAAAAUGUUAUUCUGAUUGCAUAGAUUAGCAAAAUAUUGCAUCAAUAUAAUGUUCCAUUUUUAUUAAUUUUUGUUAUAUUCUAAAUGACCGUUUUAUAAUUCUGUCUUGGACAACUGGGCCACAGUUAGAAUCCACAUAGACAGGGAGGUUCUUAGGUGUGCCAUUUGUAGAAUAAAGGGCAAUCAAGUUAAUAUUCGGGGUAAAUUUUCAUUGCAUUCUAACCUAUGAAGUUUGAUAAAGUAUAUUAUUAUUGAACAACUCUAACACUAAGAUUUCCUAAAAGUAACUUACAACAAAAAAUGAACUAUGUGCUCAAUAUUCACAUAAAGUCAUGAUUAUUCUCUUCUUGCAUUCAUAUAAAAGUUCCCAGGGGGAAGAAAAUAUAUCUAAAAAUUAGACUAGAAACUUGGCACUUUUUAUGUAUUGUAGAUACACUUUCAUAUAUUGUAAAUACAUCUGUUAAAGAUAAAACUAAGUUUCUAACAUAGCACUACAAGGAAACUUUGGAUAAAUAUUUUUAAAAAGAAAAUGUUAAUAGGAUAACUUAAGAUUUUGUAUAUACUUAUUGGAAGACAGGAAGAAACUAGGCAGUAAAUAUUCCUACCUGACGUGCAACCAUUGUCAAUCAGGUUUUGUUAAACUGUCAAAUUUGAUUUUGAAAUUUUAGUUUGCCCAAAUAAUAUCUUGAAAAUGCUCUGAAUUUUACUAGAACAUAUUCAUAGAAAGUGUAAUGUAUCUACCAGGCUCUAUGUUUGUGUUUGCCAACAUUAGAAAAACAAAGUAAGUUGCGCUAUAAUGAGUGAAACUAAGGAAAAUGAGAUUUUUCUGACUCCCAUUCCCUCUCUUAAAAAGUAAAAUAUUUAAGCUUUUUUUAUUAAAGGAAAAAUGGGUACAGAAUACUCUAUUGCCCUCCAAAUGUCCAACAUUUUUAAAGCCAUGUUGUCCAACAAUGUUUAUACAGAAAAUAGAAUGCAUAGGUUUAAUAUAGAUAGCAAUGUAUAUGUAGGCUCAUUUGUGGGAGAUUGCAAACUUUAUGUGCCCCCAGUUCUCCUUGGUUUUGUAGGAAAGCUAAAAGAAAACCUUGUACUCUCACUAAUAAUGAAAUUCAUAGCCAAUUUAGAAAGGGAAAAUAACCUGAAAACCAAAAUACCUCAUUCAUCUGAAGAUGCCUGGAAUAAAAUAUGGAAUUCUUCUGUACCUACCUCCCCCUUACAGACUUUUCUCCUAUUUUGAGAGAGAAAUUCAAGAAGAAGAAUACAGCUUGUUCUCUUUCCACAAAUGAUACUUUGUCUAAGGGAAUAGGAGAUACCAAGAAACAGUAUCUUUAAAAAAGUAAGCUGCCCACAGGCCUUCUUGGAGAAUGAAGAAUAUCAGCCCCAUUCAGGGUUUACCAAUGUCUCUCUGAGGUGACAAUACAUUCUGGUUUUCCAGGACAGUCCUGGCUUAGGUCUGCUGUCCUUCUAUAAAUAUUAACAAUGAUCCCUCUUAUUUCCAAACGUGUCCCAGUUUAGACAACAAAUUAUACAGUGUCUGCCCCCAACACACACACACACACCCCACCAUCUUUAUGGGUUGUUGUUGUUUUCUUGUUGUUUUUAAUUUUGUAGAAUUGGCUUUGUCUUCUCCAAAGCAGAUAACAGCUUAAACUAAAGAGCCUAGCUACUUCUUUCUGACUGAGCAGGGUCAUAGUAAACAGAGAAGAAUGGAUCACUUCCUCCUCUGAAAUCUCCAUCAAUCCACUUUCUGUCCAACUAUCUCUCUACCCAGCCUAUUUUUGGUCCUAGUUUUCCUCUCAUAACCCCUGGGCUGUGAGUCCUGAGUUCUGCCUUCAUAUGGCAGAGCAAGCUAGUCAUUAUUAUGCCAGGUUAGGUGGUGGGGCAAGACAAAAGAUAGCUCUUGGGGACACUUGCUUGGUCUGUAGAGAUCCACAGGGCACUAGUAGGGUAUUAGAGCAUUUAUUGGUUUCUUUCUUCCUUGAGUUGAGUUACUUCUAUCCCAAAACAGACAGGUCUUACGUUAACCUUCACCUUAAAAAGGAUAUUGCCUUUUUUCCUUCUGCUUCACAAAUUUGCUCCAACACUAAUUCCCUUGCAUUUGAUUUCAUCAUUAUGAUUGUUCAUCAACCAUUCUUCACGAAAAAUCCUCACAUCACGUCAUAUAAAGGUUUUAUUAUUUUUAAUGGAAAAUAACAUUGAGAGAUUAUUUUCCUUUUUCAUAAAAUUUCCCUUUUUCCCUCCCUCUAUUCUCUUCACUAACAUUGGAAAUUAAACAAGUUUUACAGGCUCUAUUGUUAUUAACCCUCAAAUCUAUUCUUCAGAGAAUAUAUGAUCAGCCUGUGUUUACUAUGCACCUACUCUUAUACCAGAAACUGUGAAUACAAAUACAUAUAUUUCCUACUUCUCUCUUUAAUUGGGGCACACAGUCCCAUGGUCCAUUCUGCAUUUUUCAAAAUUGAAUAUAAUUGCAACACCUGAUAGGUUUUGCCACUUAGAAUUCUGAAAAUAAAUCAACUCUGUUCUAAACCUUAAGUUUCCACUAUUAUUGCCAAACUCUGGACUGAUACAAUAAGCCUUUUAAAAGGUGAAUUUAACACUUCACCUAUUAUGGUUAUUUAAGUAAAAUGAGUUUUCAAAUAUUUCCCCCAGGAGAAAUAUAAAGGACUAUGCAAAAAUAGAAGGAGAAAAAGGUUAGUUAGAGGUCCAGAAGGAGAAUUAAAACAUGGAAUUGAUAAAUUCACCUACUGAUUUAUGAUGUUAAUGAGCAGGUACCUAUACAUUUUAUUUACUUGAAAACAUUUUGGCCAUUAACUAUUUCUGUUUUCUAAAUACAUUUGUGUUUAUAAAAUUUUAAAAUCUAUAUCACAAGACUUAGACAUGCCUUUCUUUGCAAUAAAGUAUAUAUACCUUUUUACAAAUGUAAAUUUUAUUUUGAAACUUGGCAUUUUCUUUAUAAUUCCUAAGAUAUCUUUGGGCACACAGACUACAGAUAAAUCUAUUUAAAUCAAUUCAUCAUUAUCACUGGUUUAAAUAUUUAAUGUAACCAUUGGAAUUUUUAUUCUUAUUCCUUCAGAGAAUUCUCCUUUUCUUCUAUGUUUCUGACUGCAAUACAGCCCGAUAUUGUUAUUCCCUAUAUCUUAAUGAAAAGCAAGCUGUCAGCAAAAUGCAUUUAUAGUUUCCAGAUGUUUAACAAUCUCUUUCUUCUUUUCUUUUUUGUUAUUAUUUUUAUUUAUGUGAAGUUAGUUAGCUGAGGUACCAAAAAAGAGACAAAGACAGUAUUAAAAAGUGUGCAUAAAGCACUUAUUUUUGUACUUUAGUACAAUGUUUUAUAGAACUUUGUGAUCUAUCUAAAUAUAUUAAGUAAAAUUACACCAUUCACUUGUUGGGAAAAUAAUCUUUGGUUUGGAAGAUAUUAACAUAAUGGGCAUCUUAGAAUCAUAAAUCACAUGAAAUGAGAGACAAUGCAAUAUUGUAUAAUUCCUGGAUGAUGCAAUUGUUUUAAUUGAAUUUUCAAGUGCCAUUAUAAAGUUUUAAAAAUUAUCAA